GUCAGUUCCGCGGGGGGCUGUCGGGGAACCAUGGCUGCCCCGAGAGACAAUGUCACUUUAUUAUUCAAGUUAUACUGCUUGGCAGUGAUGACCCUGAUGGCUGCAGUCUAUACCAUAGCUUUAAGAUACACAAGGACAUCAGACAAAGAACUCUACUUUUCAACCACAGCCGUGUGUAUCACAGAAGUUAUAAAGUUAUUGCUAAGUGUGGGAAUUUUAGCUAAAGAAACUGGUAGUCUGGGUAGAUUCAAAGCAUCUUUAAGAGAAAAUGUCUUGGGGAGCCCCAAGGAACUGUUGAAGUUAAGUGUGCCAUCGUUAGUGUAUGCUGUUCAGAACAACAUGGCUUUCCUAGCUCUUAGCAAUCUGGAUGCAGCAGUGUACCAGGUGACCUACCAGUUGAAGAUUCCGUGUACUGCUUUAUGCACUGUUUUAAUGUUAAACCGGACACUCAGCAAAUUACAGUGGGUUUCAGUUUUUAUGCUGUGUGCUGGAGUUACGCUUGUACAGUGGAAACCAGCCCAAGCUACAAAAGUGGUGGUGGAACAAAAUCCAUUAUUAGGGUUUGGCGCUAUAGCUAUUGCUGUAUUGUGCUCAGGAUUUGCAGGAGUAUAUUUUGAAAAAGUUUUAAAGAGUUCAGAUACUUCUCUUUGGGUGAGAAACAUUCAAAUGUAUCUAUCAGGGAUUAUUGUGACAUUAGCUGGCGUCUACUUGUCAGAUGGAGCUGAAAUUAAAGAAAAAGGAUUUUUCUAUGGUUACACAUAUUAUGUCUGGUUUGUCAUCUUUCUUGCAAGUGUUGGUGGCCUCUACACUUCUGUUGUGGUUAAGUACACAGACAACAUCAUGAAAGGCUUUUCUGCAGCAGCGGCCAUUGUCCUUUCCACCAUUGCUUCAGUAAUGCUGUUUGGAUUACAGAUAACACUCACCUUUGCCCUGGGUACUCUUCUUGUAUGUGUUUCCAUAUAUCUCUAUGGAUUACCCAGACAAGACACUACAUCCAUCCAACAAGGAGAAACAGCUUCAAAGGAGAGAGUUAUUGGUGUGUGAUUUUAGCCUCACGUGAGACUCCUUUUAAGACUAAACCAUUUGCAUUAAACUAGAGCCUUAAGUCAAUCUCAGAAGGUAGCAUAAACAAAUAAAAAUUAACUGUAUGGCAUGAUCAGUGCGGUUAUGUGGAAACAACAACAAACAAACGAAGCUAUCUGAGUGAACUGCUAAUACAGAAACUUAAUGUAGACCUGUUUGGGGUCUACUAUUGUUUUAGAAUGAAGGAAUUGUAUUAUUGUGUGUAUAUAUAAUUUGUAAAUAAAAAGUAUGGAGAUGAUACGGUGUUAAAAAAAAUCAUGGUAAGGCUACAAUACUCAAGUAACAAGGUUUGGGACAAUGUCUAAGGGUUAAAGUGCCAAAGCCAUUUCUGUACUAACUGUUCUCUUGUUCCGGUACCGGGGAGAAGGAUGACCCCUCCUUAUUCUCCAAUUCAUGUACAGUAUUUUGUCCUAGCAGCAUAAAGACCUAGCUCUUUUCUUACAAGAGGCAGAAACAAGACAGGCUAGUUCAUAAACAAACUGUGUAACUUCUCAAAAUGAAUCUAUUUCAUAACUCGGACAAUUUCUGGGUGGUGACUGAGUACCCCUUUAGUGAGUACCCCUUUAGUGCUAUAUUUGUGCCAUUCAUUAUCUGGUUCAUAUUUCUUUUCUGUUAGAUGAUACACAUUUCUUCAAAAAAAUUUCUAAUGUCACUUUUGUACUUUUUUAAAUAAAGUAUGUUUAACUGUUGGGCUCUCAAUAAUUUGUGAAAUUUCAGUGUUUUCUAUAAUGUUAAUGGGGAAAUUCAGCAAUAAACUUUAUUUGUAAGAAA